UUGCAUCCUGUUUCUGUCUGAAAACCCUUGUCUUUCUGAAUCCAUCUUUCAGUCUCUCACAUUCUGUCUUUCCCCUCCUCCUUCACCUUCCCUCCGUCCCUCUCCCUUGCGCACUUGCCGGGUACCAGCUGAGUGCAUCCUUUUCCCAAACCUGCUCUGCUUCCAAGGGGCCCUUUUCUGUCUCCUCCACCUGUCCCCAUGUUUUGGGGACUGCCUGGAAAUCCGGGACACCCUCCUGAGGAGGGAGCUGGUGCCCAACGGCACCUCUUAGGAUGAACCCAGCCAGCUGCGUUCCUGGCCUCUGCAGAAUGGCAUACAGAAGGCAUUUUAAGCAAGCGAGCUGAGCUCGCCGCAGGACUCCGACUACCAGGCACCGGCAAGAUGUGGGAAUCCUGAAAGGUUGGCGCUGAAGAUCCUGCAGUUGGUGUGUGCAAGCUGGCAGCCAGGCCGCUGCCGGAGGAAGGGGGUCCUCUGUGCUUUGCAUGUCCCUGGGUAUUUGGGAAACUUGGCAGCCGGUUGCUCUAAGUGAACCCUGACUCUGGAGUAGGCACUGGGCACCCUGGCGGAGAGGACAGAGCCGGAGACAAGGACUGGCCUCAGGGAGUUUCCAGUUCAAAUAGGAACAGACCCGAUCACACGCGAUACGCUCACCCUCAGACACAUUGCUGCUGCCUGCAUUUCCUCCGGGCUGCCAUCCCCCUUCCCCUACCCUGGCCUCUGUCUGCCACGACUGCCCUUGUCUACCUGCCAAGCUCUAAUUAUCGUUAAACAUCCCGUCACUGCUUCCCGGAAAUCUUUAACUUCCACCCAAGAACAGCUAACACUAUACGCCCUCCUCUACCUGCAGAAAUCACUUGGACCCUCUGACAUCACAUGUCCAACCGACCUCUUUCUCCACAUUUGCCCGUGAGCUGCACUUCAUUUUGCAAGGACAUAAAGAAGACUAUUCACGCAACUACAUGCAAAAUGACUGGCUGGGAUUCCUAAAACGCCAAUGUCUUUUAAAAGGCAAAAGGGCUGAGAAAUGGUUCCAGGUUAAAAGAGAUUAAAGAGCCAUGAGCCCAAAUGCAAUGUUUGAUCCUAGGAUGAAGCCUGGAUCAGGGGAACAGAAAACACUUGUGGGCUGGGCUCAGUGGCUCAUACCUGUAAUCCCAGUGCUUUGGGAGUCCGAGGGAGGAGGAUCACUUGAAGUCAAGAGUUAGAGACUAGCCUCAGGAAUAUAGGGAGACCCCAUCUCUACAAAAAAUAAAUAUAAAAAUAAACUAACCAGACAUAGUGGUGUGUGCCUGUGAUCCCAGCUACUCAGGAGGCUGAGGCAAGAGGAUCACCUGAGCCCAAGAGUUCGAGGCUGCAGUGAGCCAUGAGCCAUGAUCAUGCCACUGCACUCCAGCCUAGGUGAUAGAGCGAGACCCUGUCUCUAAAAAAAAAAAAAAAAAAAAAAACAAUUAAAGAAGUUUUAGGGAUAAGUGGGAAUAUCUGAAUAUAGAUUGUAUGUUAGAUAAUAGUAUUUAUAGUAUUUUUAUGUCAUGAAUAUGCCAAUAAUAAAUAAAUUAAAAAAAGAUAAUAGUAUUUUAUUAAUGGUACCUUCAUGAGAGUGACUUUGUAUCUCAGAUCAUUUGUACUGAGGUUAUGUAAGAGAACAUUCUUGUUCUUAGAAGAUACAGGCUGAAGGAUUCAAGGAUGAAAUAUCACAAUGUCCACAACUAACUCAAAUAAUUCAGAAGACAGAUAAUAGAGUGGGCACGAGUGUGGCAAAAUGUUAACAGUUUCGAGGAUUACAAGCGGCUGUGGAACUAUGUUCAUAACUUUUAUGUGGGUCUGAAGAUUUUCCAGUGCCCAGGCUGGGCACUCUGCUUAGCUUUGCGCGUGGAUUAUCUCAUUUCAUCCUCAGAGCAGCUUGGGGAUGGGAGAGCUCUAUCACACCCAUUUUCCAGUGGAGAAAACAGAGGCACAGCUAGUUGUAAGCCCAGGCCACAUUAUGCCCCCACCCCCUGUUUUGUGAAAUUUAGUACUAAAGAUACUACAUGGCUGUGUGAUGUCGGGCAAAUCACUUAACCUCUCUGUGAUCUGUUUCCUUUUUUCUUUUUUUUGCUACGAGUGGAUAAUUAUAAUAUCAGAAGGUUGUUCUGAUGGGUAUUAUGAUAUAUAAAGAACUUAGAACAGGGUUUGGCCUAAAGUAAGCGCUGAGCAAGUGUCUGCUGUUGCUGCUGCUAAUUGUAUUUGUUGCUGCAGUCGUGAUCCCAGCACCCUCACCUUGGCCAGUGAUGGGGAAACCUGAAGGGUGUUUUUUCUUCUGUACCCAGGGCGUGCUUCAUGGGUUUGUGAUCUAUAUGGUCACACAGGGUCCCGUGUUCAGAAGAUCCCCCCAUGUCACUGACUUGCAAUUCGUAACCAUUUUCUCACAAGGGGCCUCGAAUAUUUAUUUUAUGCACUGGGUCCCACACAUCAUGUAGCCAGCCCUGUCUGCUCUCCCUUUUUAUUGGAUCCCGUUGAGAGCCUCUCCUAGACUAAACUACUUGUGCCUACGUCAUUGCAGCAGACAGGCCCAGGCAGGCCGUGGCAUUUCAGCAGGUCAGAUUGUAUGUUCCUGUGACCACACUCCAAUUCUGAUGCAAUGCGUCAGCCCGCACAGGCCAGUACAGUAGCCGUUCAUCACAUCUGGUCAUUGAGCAUCUGAGACGUGGCUAUUCUAAACUGUGAUGUGCUGUGAGUGUGAAAUUCACACCAGAUUUUGAAGACUUAGCACACAUCCGAAAAAGAAAUGCAAAAUAUCUUAUUAAUAACUAUAUUGAUGGCCGGGCACGGUAGCUCGCGUCUGUAAUCCCAGCACUUUGGGAGGCCAAGGCGGGUGGAUCACUUGAGGUCAGGAGUUUGAGACCAGCCUGACCAACAUGGUGAAACUUUGUCUCUACUAAAAAUACAAAAAUUAGCCAGGAGUGAUGGCACACACCUGUCAUCCCAGCUACUCGGGAGGCUGAGGCAGGAGAAUCGCUUGAACCUGGGAGGCGAAGGUUGCAGUGAGCCGAGAUUGUGCCACUGCACUUCAGCCUGGGCAACAAGAGCAAAACUCCAUCUCAAAAGUAAUAAUAAUAACUAUAUUGAUUAUGUAUCAAAAUUAUUACAUUUUAGAUACAAUGGGUUAAAUAAGAUACAUGAAAAAAAUUGGUUUCAGCUGUUUUUGCUUUUUUCAUAUGGCUACCAGAAAAUGUAAAAUUACCUAUGUGGUUUGCAUUGAAAGCUUGUGUUAUAUUUCUUUUGGGCAGUACUGUCUUAGAGCAUACUACCUGUGCCUUCAUUGUGACUCCAAACCAAACCAGACCAGCAGGUGACAGUGCAGUGAAUUGAUUUCUAAGUUACAUUAAUACACACUGGCCCUGGUGCUGUAGCUUAGACCAGAGUCUCCCAAUCAAUCCAUCAGGCACCUCUUUCUGUUCCUUCUUUUCUGUUCCUUUCUCUCUUAAGAUAGUCCAAGACACUGAUUUUUAUACCCAGUGAGUUUGUCAAGUAGCCUAAAGAUAUUUUUGAGGCAACGUAUUGGGUAAAAAGAAACUGAAGUUGGAAUCAGAAGGACUAAUUUAAGAAUUAAAUUAAAAUCCCAAAUCACCUCUUUUUUUUUUUCUUUUAGAGAUGGGGUCUCGCUCUGUCACCCAGGCUGAUCUCAAUCUCCUGGGCUCAAGCGAUCCUCUCACCUUGGCCUCCCAACAUGCUGGGAUUACACAUCAGGUCCCAGGUCACCUCUUCUCCAUGAGGUGAGCUUGGGCAUGUUAUUUCUCUGUGCAAGGAAACAGAACAGCACUAGCUUUAAAGCCUCACAGACCCGAGUUUGAAGACUGGCUCUGCCGUUGACAAGCUGUGUGACACAGGAUAAGCCACAACCCUCUCUGAACCUCAGUCUCAUCCUCAGUCUCAUAGCGCUGAUGAUGCAUACUGUGUAAUACUGUUGCAAGAAUGGAAUAAGAUGAAGCAGAACAAAUGUCCAACCCAGCAACUGGCACAUGGCAGGUGUGCGCUUAAUCCCUGCAUUCUUAGUGGGAUCAGUAUUCCCAAGAGAGUGAACAUUUAUGGGAAAGAAAAGAAAUCUUACUCUUUAUGAAUAAAGUACAGAUAUAAAAUACAAUACAUAAGCAGAUGUACAAUUUAUCUGUGGAAUUAAAAUUUCAUGGGGUAUGUAGCUAAUAAAGAAUCUUUAGGGGAAUGGCAAUGAAAAAAAGUUUGAGAAACAUUGCAUUAAUCUGACGGAUGGGACUCAGAGGUUGCUUUUCAGUUCAGUUCCUGUAGUUGUCAGAGUAUAGGGCUGAAACUCCAUGAUUGAAUUCAACAAGUGUUUUUGAGCACCUACAAUAGCCAGACACCGUUCUGGACCCUGGAAAUGGAGGGCACCCUCCAGGUACAUGCUUCCCAGAGCUGGUCUCUGAGGUCCCCUGAGCCAGCCCCUGCCUCUGGGAAGAUGACCCCUAAAUGGCAGCCUCAGUCAGGGGGCAGGGUUUUAGAGAACAACAGGAAUAGAAGUAUUUGCCUCCCAGGAGUAGAUAAGACGGUGUAUGUGAAACCUUGACACGAUUGGCAUUCAUUCGUAAAAUCAGAGCAGAUACCUGCACACACAGGCAUAAAUGAAAGAUACUUUGAAUUACAGAAAAGUUAAGGUCUUUGCAAGUGCAUGUAGGAAUGCUGCCAGGCACACAGCGUGACUCCAGCCACCAACAAAGUGUUUCCAAGUCUGGAGCUGUGUGGUCCUUGAAGGAAAUAUAAAUGUUUCACUUGUUAUACGCUGUGAUUUUUGCGUACUUAGCGGUUUCUGGAGUCCGUGAAAGUGGUUUGUUUUCUCUGAACGGGAAGUGCGUUUCCUCCAAUCACACCGACCUGAUUUGUUUGUUGCUUGUUGGGCCUCCCCACGGGAACACGAGAUCCCACAGAACACAGCAGGACGUGUCCUUGUUUACUGAGGAAUCUCUGGGGCUCGGCACAGGUGUGCAGAAAGCAUUUAUUGAACUGAACAAACAGAUUUUACAAGCCGGACCUUCUGUGGCGUUGGCCCGGGUAGCUACUUCAGCAUGGGUCCAAGCAUCCUUUCUAAGCCAAUUCCAUUCUUUCACUCCUCCUCCCUUGUAGGAUCAGAAAUCCAAAGCUAGCUUAUCCUUUUGCAGAUGUUUCUUUCCAUAUUAUUUCCUACCUCCAGAACAAAGGCUAUCUGUGUCUCACAUUCGGAGGCUUGGAUGUGAAGCCCUGUCUGUUCAUUUUUCUCUCCAGUUUUUUCACAGGCUGGGUAACUACCUGCCUGCUAGCAACGAUGUGUUCGUUCUCCCUGGAUUCCUGAUUGAGGUGGGCAGAGAGGACUCUGAGACAGGAGCAUGAGGAUGAGGCAGAUCAGCUUCUUUCUCAUGAAAUCUGGAUGUUGAGGCUGGUAGCAGGACCACCGCAUGUGCCAAUAGUCUUUAGCAGCUCAUCAGGCCAUAGAAGAAGUGCCUUUACUAACUUCAAGUCCAGCCUGGGAAACGUAGUGAGACCUUGUCUCUCCCUGUCUAAAAAAAGAAGAAGAAAGAAGGAGGAGGAGGAGGAGAAGGAGAAGGAAAAAAAGAAGUUGUUCACAAUUUUUGUUUACUCGUUUACUUAUUUUUGAGAUGGAGUUUCACUCUUGUCGCCAGGUUGGAGAGCAGUGGCACGACCUCUACUCACUGCAACAUUCGGUUCUCAGGUUUAAGCAAUUCUCCUGCCUCAGCCUCCCAAGUAGCUGGAACUACAGGCACCUGCCACCACGCCCAGCUGAUUUCUGUAUUUUUUUGUAGAGUUGGGACUUCACCAUUUUAGCCAGGCUGGUCUCGAACUUUUGACCUCAGGUGAUCUGCCUGCCUCGGCCUCCCAAAGUGCUAGGAUUACAGGCGUGAGCCAUCGCGCCCAGCCAAAAUGCACAAUUUUAAAGAGCUCUUUGGAAACAGAAAAUGGCCUGCAACAGGCAUCUCUUCCACAUCCUAUGUACUUUCUUCAAUUGACCCUAAGCCAGUUGAGUGCCUCCUGACCCCACAAAUAGAUUUCAUUCUUCCCAUUUUACAGAUGCAGAAACUAAGGCACUGAUGAGUUCAGCAACUUGCCUAGGUAAUAUAUAUGGCCCAGCCACACUUUAGACCCAAUUUCUGGCUCUUGUUACUUUCCCCACAUCAUUCUCAGUCUUUCUUAGGAAUGGACAUUUGCCUGUUUCCAAGAACAGUAUUUCUGUCUCCCUAUACAAGUCACUGAUAAUUUUAUGAUGCCCAAGAGGCAGGUGAUAGGAAGUCAUGCCUGCAGGGAGAGAGGGCUGGGGCCCAUGCGGAGGGGAAAGUCAGAAGAGGCUGUUGCAGCUGAAGUCGGAGGAGAAAAGUGGAUGUGAGAUAAAGCCUCUGUCCCUGUGCCACUGCCCCUGAAUGGGGCCCUGUUAACCCCAUCUGCACAGGCCCACGGCUCCGGCUUUAUGGGUUGCUAUGGCAACCCCUGGCCUUGACAACUGAAGUGCACUUGGCUGAGUGUGUCUUUGUGUCCCUUUGAGUCUGCAGAGAAGCCAGCAGCUGGGGCUGCAGACGGGAAAGGAAUGUCCUCAGCGUCUGCCAGCACUUUUGUCUUGGUCCCAACGGCUGAUAGGAAAAUGAGAGGCAGGGUCUUUUCUAGAGAGAUCUGGGGGGUCCAUUUCUAGCCGAUGAUGCAUGCAAAGAGUUCGUGUUCACAGGACCUGGGAAGCAGCGGAGUAGAAAGGGUGGCAGCACGCAAAGGGUGUCCCUGUCCCUCAAGGGGUCAUGGCCUCCAUGUUGCUCGCCCAGCGCCUGGCCUGCAGCUUCCAGCACAGCUACCGCCUGCUGGUGCCUGGAUCCAGACACAUUAGUCAAGCUGCAGCCAAAGUCGACGUUGAAUUUGAUUAUGAUGGGCCUCUGAUGAAGACGGAAGUCCCAGGGCCUAGAUCUCAGGAGUUAAUGAAACAGCUGAAUAUAAUUCAGAAUGCAGAGGCUGUGCAUUUUUUCUGCAAUUACGAAGAGAGCCGAGGCAAUUACCUGGUUGAUGUGGACGGCAACCGAAUGCUGGAUCUUUAUUCCCAGAUCUCCUCUGUCCCCAUAGGUUACAGCCACCCCGCCCUGCUGAAACUCAUCCAACAGCCUCAAAAUGCGAGCAUGUUUGUCAACAGACCCGCCCUCGGAAUCCUGCCUCCGGAGAACUUUGUGGAGAAGCUCCGGCAGUCCUUGCUCUCGGUGGCUCCCAAAGGGAUGUCCCAGCUCAUCACCAUGGCCUGCGGCUCCUGCUCCAAUGAAAACGCCUUAAAGACCAUCUUCAUGUGGUACCGGAGCAAGGAAAGAGGGCAGAGGGGCUUCUCCCAGGAGGAGCUGGAGACGUGCAUGAUUAACCAGGCCCCUGGCUGCCCCGACUACAGCAUCCUCUCCUUCAUGGGCGCGUUCCAUGGGAGGACCAUGGGUUGCUUAGCGACCACGCACUCUAAAGCCAUUCACAAGAUCGACAUCCCUUCCUUUGACUGGCCCAUCGCACCGUUCCCACGGCUGAAAUACCCUCUGGAAGAGUUUGUGAAAGAGAACCAACAGGAGGAGGCCCGCUGUCUGGAAGAGGUGGAGGAUCUGAUUGUGAAAUAUCGGAAAAAGAAGAAGACGGUGGCCGGGAUCAUCGUGGAGCCCAUCCAGUCCGAGGGUGGAGACAACCACGCAUCCGAUGACUUCUUUCGGAAGCUGAGAGACAUCGCCAGGAAGCAUGGCUGCGCCUUCUUGGUGGACGAGGUCCAGACCGGAGGAGGCUGCACGGGCAAGUUCUGGGCCCAUGAGCACUGGGGCCUGGAUGACCCAGCAGACGUGAUGACCUUCAGCAAGAAGAUGAUGACUGGGGGCUUCUUCCACAAGGAGGAGUUCAGGCCUAAUGCUCCCUACCGGAUCUUCAACACCUGGCUGGGGGACCCGUCCAAGAACCUGUUGCUGGCUGAGGUCAUCAACAUCAUCAAGCGGGAGGACCUGCUAAAUAAUGCAGCCCAUGCCGGGAAGGCCCUGCUCACAGGACUGCUGGACCUCCAGGCCCGGUACCCCCAGUUCAUCAGCAGGGUGAGAGGACGAGGCACCUUUUGCUCCUUCGAUACUCCCGAUGAUUCCAUACGGAAUAAGCUCAUUUUAAUUGCCAGAAACAAAGGUGUGGUGUUGGGUGGCUGUGGUGACAAAUCCAUUCGUUUCCGUCCCACGCUGGUCUUCAGGGAUCACCACGCUCACCUGUUCCUCAAUAUUUUCAGUGACAUCUUAGCAGACUUCAAGUAAAGAAGCCAUUUCCACUACAGUGAGAAAGCCCGGAUCCCAACAGUUGUCAAAUUGAUUAGUUUGCCUAAUUCAUGUUUUCACUUAAAAGUAUCAGAGGUGAAUGCACAGUGAAGGGUGAUUUGUGGGGAGGGAGCAUUUUUGGUGGUCUUGGGGGAGGGGAGGGGAGGGAAGGGCUGGUGUUGAUUUUCCUCCCUGCAGAGCCAAUGGUGCACAUUGGUUUAAGCCCAGAGAUCCUGCUUGAGCCCUGGACUCAUCUUGGGAAGGGCCAUGGGAGGUCCUGGCUAGAGUUCUGCCCAACCUUGACCAACCCCAGCAAUUUUUCCAAAAGCCAGUCAAGGGCAUUACAUUUGUUCCUGGGACUGGCAGCUGGGCCUCCUGGGUGCCAGUCCAUCUCAAGUGCCAUAUUCUGUGAUCACGGAUGUUGGCUCCCCCUCGCCCUAUGCAAGCAAACACACUCUCACCUCCUCUCCCAGCCUCCCGGAGCUCUGAGCACGCCCCACGCAUGGUGCAGGAGGGACUGGACAGAUCUGAGGAAGGCCGUAAAAUGGGGACAGGAGGAUUCAGCUCAGGAGUAAGGGAAGAGGUCCUCUGGCCCCCUGAAGAUGAGAAUCACCCCUCUCAGUGCACCUGGGGAUCCCCCUAAACUGUGAAUUCUGCCCUGGACAGGGCUUUGCCCUUGGAGGAUCCCCAGGUGGCCUUACCCGUGAUUCUUACUCGGCAUCCUCCAUUCCCCAAACUCCCUCCUCCCUGUUAAAUGUCAACCUAGACCUGGACCUGGGUGGGAGGAAACUGUAGCCUGAGUGUCCACAGGGACACACGUGAGCCACAGGGCUAGAAGCACAGGCCCGUCACCCCAGGAGGAAAAGCCCAGGGUCUGGGGCAGCAGAGCCAUCGCAUCAUGUUUCCCAGGGCAACUUGAGGUCUGACUUUUGGCUCCCUCGCCCUAAGAGGCUCUUCCUCUCUUUUGCUCAUCCACCUUCACACCACUUGUGAGCUGACCCCCAGGAACAGCUUGGCUGUUCCACCAGAGCAGAGGGAAUCAUUGCUGGACUGGAUUUCUUCUGGAGGGAAGCACCAUGAAUUAAAGGUGCCAGAGCUCCAUGCAUGGAAAAGUGGCCUGUUGGUUCAACGUGGUUUCCUUGUACUUGAUCCUCCUGAAAUGAGAGAUUUUCCUGAGAUGACUGAGUAUGGAGAUUACCAGGCAGAUGAUACCGAAAUGCUUAAAGGGGCUGUGGCUGAGGCUGUAGCAUCUCUGCUGGAGGUGAGACACUCUGGGAACUGAUUUGACCUCGAAUGCUCCUAAAAGAGAACUUGAUAGCCUGACAGCAGAGAAGUAUUAUUUGGUGGGGAGUCUGAGAAAGCCUGGCUUGUAUUAUCUGUCCAAAAGGAAGCCUCUUCAUCUCCCGGUGCCUUGGUUGACUAUUUUGGAAAUAGGCAUAUCAAGGUUCCUGAUUCAGCACUUUGCUCUUUUAAUAACAAAUCGUCCAAAGAUCUCAAAGUAAGGGUUUUUUUUUUUAGCUUCCACUCUUCCGCAGACUUGGUCAUCGACCUAUUUUUGUUGAAGAAUGAAAGGCAAUGACAAGUUUAACAUAUACAAAUUCGUGAAUUCUUGUUCAUUUUGCAUUCCUGCAGUCAGUGCUAAUCCGUCGUUCUUAAUCAGGAGUUCUGCCAGGUUUAAGGUCACCUGCACUCCCAGCCAAGUGGUGAUGUAUGCCUCCCACUCUCUGCAAGGUUUUCCUCAUUUUUAUAUUCAUUUAUUCAUCAUUCAUUCAUUCACCUAACUUUCAUUAAAUAGCUGCACCAUCCCAGGCCCUGUGCGGAGCAUCGGGAAUACAAAGAUGAGAUAAAACAUUGUCCCUGCCCCCGGGGGCUCACAUGCCACUGGAAACAACAGACUCUUAAACUAACAAUUCAAGCAGGCGCCAAGUGCUAUGACAGAGGUGUGAAUAAAAGCAUCAGGAAAUCGGAUGGAGAACCACCAUUCACCCAAGGGUCAGAGGAGGUUUCAAAGAAAAGGUGUCAUUGGAGCAGUGUUUUGCAGAAUGAGCCAGAGUUCACCAAGCAGGCAAGGCAAGGAAGGGUGUUGCAGAGAGGGAACAGCAUAUGCAAAGGCGUAUCAGUUCAUGGCAUCACAUCUUUCACUGGGGAAGCCAGUUUCCACAGGCAGCAUCCCAAGGUUCAAUAAGGCCUUAUUUAACAAGCAAGCAAAAUGCAAACCAAACCAUUAUUCAUUUAUUGGCUUAAGUAUGCUUUCUCCUGAAAACUUUAGCAUUGGGUGCAAAUAUUCAGUAUGGUUCUCGGAGUCCAAAGGGUUUUAAGCCAGGGCACAACCAGAAAAGUGGCUCUCUUUGGUAGGGAGAGGGGCUCCAAUAUUUCGUUCUCUCCCCAUGGGGCACUGACAGAGAAAUGAAAUAGUUUUAUCUGGAAAAUUCCAGAGCUAUUAUUUACUCCUUACCAAGGGAAGUUACUUCUUGUAAAAACUUUUAAGCCAUUUAUCAACAAGUUCUUGUUGACUCAGGGCAUAAUGAGUUCCUGAGACAUGCUCUUUUGGGGGCUGGGGCUUUAGCUAGAAGAAUUUCAAGGAAAAGAAUUCUCAGCAGAGCUCAAGAUUGUAGAAACUCAGCAGAAGCUGGUAAAAACAUGGGGAGCCCGGAGGACAGGCUGCUGUCCAGGGCAGAGGCCAUGAAGAAGUGCUUCCGUGGCCGACAGUCUGGAAAUGAAUCCAUCAUACAUUAGUGCCAUAGAGUUUAGUAACCGUCCAGCAAGUGUCAUCACUUUUACAGAAAACAAGGUCCAGUAAUAGCAAGUCUUAGUACAUCCUCACUUUUAUUAUAAAUGGGUGUUUUUUCAUAAUUUUUACUGACGCUCAGUAACCAUGCAAAAUUGUGUAUAGCAUUAAUGUAUCUACAUACCUACACCUAUCUAUAUAUAAGCUCAUGGUAGAAAACCAUAGCUAAGUAGCAUCGCAGACUUAAGCGUACAAAGUGAUCUUGUUCACAAGUAAUCUGUUGACAGUGCCAAUAAAUGAUAAAAAAAAAAUUAACAUGUCACAAUGUAACGGAUGACCAUAUGCACAAUUCCAUGAAUUAAAUCUGUUUCCUGUGUUAGUCAGUAUUCUUAAAUAAAAUUUAUAAUUGAAA